AAACCAGUUCACGCCGGAGCCCCGUGAGGGAAGCGUCUCCGUUGGGUCCGGCCGCUCUGCGGGACUCUGAGGAAAAGCUCGCACCAGGCAAGAAUACCCUCCAAUACCCUCGGGUGGACGCGGAUCUGUCAACAUGGGUAAAGGAGACCCCAACAAGCCGCGGGGCAAAAUGUCCUCGUACGCCUUCUUCGUGCAGACCUGCCGGGAAGAGCACAAGAAGAAACACCCGGACUCUUCCGUCAAUUUCGCGGAAUUCUCCAAGAAGUGUUCGGAGAGAUGGAAGACCAUGUCUGCAAAGGAGAAGUCGAAGUUUGAAGAUAUGGCAAAAAGUGACAAAGCUCGCUAUGACAGGGAGAUGAAAAAUUACGUUCCUCCCAAAGGUGAUAAGAAGGGGAAGAAAAAGGACCCCAAUGCUCCUAAAAGGCCACCAUCUGCCUUCUUCCUGUUUUGCUCUGAACAUCGCCCAAAGAUCAAAAGUGAACACCCUGGCCUAUCCAUUGGGGAUACUGCAAAGAAAUUGGGUGAAAUGUGGUCUGAGCAGUCAGCCAAAGAUAAACAACCAUAUGAACAGAAAGCAGCUAAGCUAAAGGAGAAAUAUGAAAAGGAUAUUGCUGCAUAUCGUGCCAAGGGCAAAAGUGAAGCAGGAAAGAAGGGCCCUGGCAGGCCAACAGGCUCAAAGAAGAAGAACGAACCAGAAGAUGAGGAGGAGGAGGAGGAAGAAGAAGAUGAAGAUGAGGAGGAAGAGGAUGAAGAUGAAGAAUAAAUGGCUAUCCUUUAAUGAUGCGUGUGGAAUGUGUGUGUGUGCUCAGGCAAUUAUUUUGCUAAGAAUGUGAAUUCAAGUGCAGCUCAAUACUAGCUUCAGUAUAAAAACUGUACAGAUUUUUGUAUAGCUGAUAAGAUUCUCUGUAGAGAAAAUACUUUUAAAAAAUGCAGGUUGUAGCUUUUUGAUGGGCUACUCAUACAGUUAGAUUUUACAGCUUCUGAUGUUGAAUGUUCCUAAAUAUUUAAUGGUUUUUUUAAUUUCUUGUGUAUGGUAGCACAGCAAACUUGUAGGAAUUAGUAUCAAUAGUAAAUUUUGGGUUUUUUAGGAUGUUGCAUUUCGUUUUUUUAAAAAAAAUUUUGUAAUAAAAUUAUGUAUAUUAUUUCUAUUGUCUUUGUCUUAAUAUGCUAAGUUAAUUUUCACUUUAAAAAAGCCAUUUGAAGACCAGAGCUAUGUUGAUUUUUUUCGGUAUUUCUGCCUAGUAGUUCUUAGACACAGUUGACCUAGUAAAAUGUUUGAGAAUUAAAACCAAACAUGCUCAUAUUUGCAAAAUGUUCUUUAAAAGUUACAUGUUGAACUCAGUGAACUUUAUAAGAAUUUAUGCAGUUUUACAGAACGUUAAGUUUUGUACUUGACGUUUCUGUUUAUUAGCUAAAUUGUUCCUCAGGUGUGUGUAUAUAUAUAUACAUAUAUAUAUAUAUAUAUAU